ACUUGAACUCCAUUUCAUCUUUUUUCAUACCAUCUCUAAGAUUGCUGCCGCAUUUGCUUGUUAAACUGAAAGCAUGUUUCUUGCAAAGGCUCUAUUGGAAGGAGCAGAUCGAGGUCUUGGAGAAGCUCUUGGAGGCCUCUUUGGAGGAGGUGGUCAGAGAAGAGAAGGAGGAGGAAGAAAUAUUGGAGGGAUAGUUGGAGGAAUUGUGAAUUUUAUCAGUGAGGCUGCAGCAGCUCAGUAUACUCCAGAACCGCCUCCCACUCAGCAGCAUUUCACCAGUGUGGAGGCCUCAGAAAGUGAGGAAGUUAGGCGAUUUCGGCAACAAUUUACACAGCUGGCUGGACCAGACAUGGAGGUGGGUGCCACUGAUCUGAUGAAUAUUCUCAACAAAGUCCUUUCUAAGCACAAAGAUCUUAAGACUGACGGUUUUAGUCUUGACACCUGCCGGAGCAUUGUGUCUGUCAUGGACAGUGACACGACUGGUAAGCUGGGCUUUGAAGAAUUUAAGUAUCUGUGGAACAACAUCAAGAAAUGGCAGUGUGUUUAUAAGCAGUAUGACAGGGACCAUUCUGGGUCUCUGGGAAGUUCUCAGCUGCGGGGAGCUCUGCAGGCCGCAGGCUUCCAGCUAAAUGAACAACUUUACCAAAUGAUUGUCCGCCGGUAUGCUAAUGAAGAUGGAGAUAUGGAUUUUAACAAUUUCAUCAGCUGCUUGGUCCGCCUGGAUGCCAUGUUUCGUGCCUUCAAGUCUCUGGAUAGAGAUAGAGAUGGCCUGAUUCAAGUGUCUAUCAAAGAAUGGCUGCAGUUGACCAUGUAUUCCUGAAGUGGGAACUGAGAAGUCAAGAUCCUCCCUGGAGGACAGGACUGAAAACCUUGCCAAGCUGUACACAGUUGCUGAUACCCUGUGCAACAGCUCUCAUUUCCUGGCAAGCUCUUUCACAACCCUACAUAUUUCUGAUCAUGUGCUGCCUUUUACUGCUGAAUUAAAACAGAUAUUUCACGAAAAA